AUUGCGCCGGUAGCAGGAUCCGCAGCGGCCGCCGCGUGAGGCUGUGGUCACGUGUUGUUUUGCCCGCUGUCGUGCGCUCAGAGUGGAGUGGGCGGGGGCGCGGGCCAAGGCAGGAGGGGGCUGGGGCGGGCAGACGAGGGUAGACAGCCUCUUCCCCCAACCCUCCCUUUCCUGAAUUCCCCCUCCUCCUCGCUCACCUUAAAACCAUCGUGCAUCACCAUGGCGAGUUGCUCCUUCACUCGCGACCAAGCGACAAGAAGACUAAGAGGUGCAGCAGCGGCGGCAGCGGCAGCUCUAGCAGCAGUGGUGACCACCCCGCUUCUUUCCUCGGGAACCCCGACCGCACUCAUUGGGACCGGGUCGUCUUGUCCGGGAGCCAUGUGGCUCUCCACGGCCACUGGCUCCCGGUCAGACUCCGAGUCCGAAGAGGAGGACCUGCCCGUCGGGGAGGAAGUCUGCAAACGCGGCUACCUGCGGAAACAGAAGCAUGGGCACAGGCGCUACUUCGUGCUCAAACUCGAGACUGCUGACGCCCCAGCUCGGCUGGAAUACUACGAAAAUGCCAGGAAGUUCCGGCACAGUGUCCGCGCCGCGGCGGCUGCAGCAGCGGCGGCCGCCUCUGGCGCCGCGAUCCCCCCGCUCAUUCCACCGCGGCGCGUGAUCACCCUAUACCAGUGCUUUUCCGUGAGCCAGCGAGCAGAUGCAAGGUACCGACACCUCAUUGCUCUUUUCACCCAAGACGAAUACUUCGCGAUGGUGGCCGAGAACGAGUCGGAGCAGGAAAGCUGGUACUUGCUGCUCAGCCGCCUCAUCCUCGAGAGCAAGCGCCGCCGCUGCGGCACGCUCGGCGCGCAGCCGGACGGAGAGCCGGCCGCGCUGGCGGCGGCAGCGGCGGCGGAGCCACCCUUCUAUAAAGAUGUGUGGCAGGUAAUAGUCAAACCCAGGGGGCUGGGGCACAGAAAAGAGCUGAGCGGCGUGUUCCGGCUGUGUCUAACCGACGAGGAGGUCGUGUUUGUGAGGCUGAACACCGAAGUGGCCAGCGUGGUCGUCCAGCUCCUGAGCAUCCGUCGCUGUGGACACUCGGAGCAGUAUUUCUUCUUGGAAGUAGGCAGGUCCACUGUCAUCGGUCCGGGAGAGCUCUGGAUGCAGGUCGAUGACUGUGUGGUUGCCCAAAACAUGCAUGAGCUGUUUUUGGAGAAGAUGAGAGCCUUGUGUGCAGACGAAUACAGAGCCCGCUGCCGCAGCUACAGCAUCAGCAUCGGCGCCCACCUGUUAACCCUGCUGUCCGCUAGGAGGCACCUGGGCUUGGUGCCGCUCGAGCCGGGAGGCUGGCUCAGAAGGUCCCGCUUUGAGCAGUUUUGCCACCUCAGGGCCAUCGGCGACGGGGAAGACGAGAUGCUUUUCACCAGGCGCUUCGUAACACCCAGCGAGCCUGUGGCCCACUCCAGGCGAGGAAGACUGCACCUGCCCAGAGGGCGCAGGUCAAGGAGAGCGGUUUCAGUGCCGGCCAGCUUUUUUCGCCGCUUAGCACCCAGCCCAGCACGUCCCCGGCACCCUGCAGAAGCCCCGAACAAUGGAGCUCGCCUGUCUUCUGAAGUGUCUGGUUCUGGCUCUGGCAACUUUGGGGAGGAAGGCAAUCCCCAGGGCAAAGAAGAUCAGGAAGGAAGCGGAGGUGACUACAUGCCUAUGAACAAUUGGGGCUCAGGAAAUGGCCGGGGCUCAGGAGGUGGCCAGGGCUCAAAUGGCCAAGGCUCCAGUAGCCAUAGCUCGGGAGGAAACCAGUGUUCAGGCGAGGGACAGGGAUCCCGAGGUGGUCAGGGCUCAAAUGGCCAGGGCUCAGGAGGAAACCAGUGCUCUAGAGAUGGCCAGGGCACCGCAGGUGGGCACGGUUCAGGUGGUGGCCAGAGACCUGGAGGUGGGCAUGGCUCAGGUGGUGGCCAGGGACCUGGAGAUGGCCAUGGCUCAGGUGGUGGCAAGAACUCUGGGGGGGGCAAAGGCUCAGGAAGUGGGAAAGGAUCCGAUGGUGAUGGUGAACGUGGAAAAUCUCUGAAGAAAAGAUCCUAUUUUGGCAAAUUAACUCAAAGCAAGCAACAGCAAAUGCCACCACCUCCACCACCUCCUCCUCCACCCCCACCAGCUGGAGGAACUGGUGGAAAAGGGAAGUCUGGGGGAAGAUUCAGACUUUAUUUUUGUGUUGACAGAGGAGCCACGAAAGAAUGCAAAGAAGCCAAAGAAGUGAAAGAUGCAGAGAUCCCAGAAGGUGCAGCUCGAGGUCCCCACAGAGCCAGAGCUUUUGAUGAAGAUGAGGAUGACCCAUACGUGCCAAUGAGGCCAGGGGUGGCCACCCCUCUUGUAAGCUCCAGUGAUUAUAUGCCAAUGGCUCCUCAAAAUGUCUCUGCUUCAAAAAAGCGCCACUCUCGAUCCCCUUUUGAAGAUUCAAGAGGGUACAUGAUGAUGUUUCCCAGAGUGAGCCCACCACCUGCUCCGAGUCCUCCAAAAGCACCUGAUACUAAUAAAGAGGAUGACUCAAAGGACAAUGACAGUGAGAGUGACUACAUGUUUAUGGCUCCUGGAGCCGGUGCAAUUCCAAAAAACCCCAGAAAUCCUCAGGGUGGCUCUUCCUCCAAAAGUUGGAGCUCCUACUUCUCUCUACCAAACCCUUUUCGGAGCUCACCUUUGGGACAGAAUGACAACAGUGAGUAUGUGCCAAUGUUACCUGGAAAGUUCCUGGGGAGGGGCCUAGACAAAGAAGUCUCCUAUAACUGGGACCCCAAAGAUGCAGCUUCAAAGCCUUCAGGUGAGGGAUCAUUCUCAAAGCCUGGAGAUGGGGGAUCACCUUCAAAGCCUUCAGAUCAUGAGCCCCCAAAGAAUAAAGCUAAGAGACCUAACCGACUUUCUUUUAUUACAAAAGGAUAUAAAAUCAAGCCAAAACCACAAAAGCCCACACAUGAGCAGAGAGAAGCUGACAGCUCUAGUGACUACGUCAACAUGGACUUCACUAAAAGAGAGAGCAAUACACCAGCUCCCUCUACUCAAGGACUACCAGAUUCGUGGGGCAUAAUUGCUGAACCCAGACAGUCAGCCUUUUCUAAUUAUGUGAAUGUUGAGUUUGGAGUGCCAUUUCCAAAUCCAGCAAACGACCUCUCAGAUCUUUUAAGAGCUAUACCACGUGCCAACCCCUUAUCUCUGGACAGUGCUAGGUGGCCACUUCCUCCCCUUCCCCUCAGUGCUACAGGUAGCAAUGCUAUUGAGGAAGAGGGUGACUACAUUGAAGUAAUUUUCAACUCAGCAAUGACACCAGCCAUGGCUCUUGCUGACAGUGCCAUUCGCUAUGAUGCUGAAACAGGUCGAAUCUAUGUGGUCGACCCAUUUUCUGAGUGCUGUAUGGAUAUUUCUCUCUCCCCCAGCCGAUGUUCUGAACCACCACCUGUAGCUAGGCUGCUGCAGGAAGAAGAGCAGGAGAGAAGACGCCCACAAAGCCGUUCUCAAAGUUUCUUUGCAGCAGCCAGAGCCGCUGUCUCUGCUUUUCCAACAGACAGCCUCGAGAGAGACCUUUCCCCAUCCUCAGCCCCGGCUGUCGCUUCGGCUGCAGAGCCGACUUUAGCCCUCAGCCAAGUUGUAGCUGCGGCCUCCGCGCUCGCCGCAGCCCCGGGCAUCGGCGCAGCAGCCGCAGCUGCUGGAUUUGACUCCGCCUCUGCCCGCUGGUUUCAACCUGUUGCUAAUGCUGCUGAUGCCGAAGCAGUAAGGGGAGCCCAAGACGUUGCCGGUGGCUCGAACCCUGGAGCCCACAACCCAUCUGCAAACCUUGCCAGAGGUGAUAACCAGGCUGGCGGGGCUGCCGCUGCAGCUGCCGCUCCGGAACCACCACCUCGCAGUCGCCGGGUGCCAAGACCCCCGGAGAGAGAAGAUUCUGACAACGACGACGACACUCACGUGAGAAUGGAUUUUGCCAGACGUGAUAAUCAGUUCGACUCUCCCAAAAGAGGAUAAAUUCCAGAAACCUUGAGUGUUCCUUUUCUCUGUCACUAGUAAUGACAGGCAAGUCACAUUUGCUGUGCCUCAUUUUCUUCUUUUAACCCCCCACCCUUCUAAAAGAGGGUGUGGUGACAACUUGAGAAUGGAUAUGAAUAUUAUUUCAAAGGUUUAAAAAGCAGUUAAAACAUUUAAUUCAUAUAUCUUAUGGGAAAUCAAGGAAAGCAAGAUAAGGCUGGAGGAAGACCUGACUCCAGGGGCAGCUUACCCUGGAAUGGUGGAAGUUUUUAAAGGGCUACUUUUCCAAAGGAAGAAGUAAGGAAGAGUAGGAGCUGUCAGACUUGGAAACAAGACUUAGAGUAAUUCUACUGUGUACAACAUUGUGGAAUGUUGUCAUCAGUGUGUCUUGAAACAUUUUCAAGAGAUGAUUGCAGAGGAUGAUGUCUCCAUAGUCUCAACUACCUUGCCUCUUAAGUAGAAUAUGCUUCUUUCCCAGUGAAGGGAAGGGAUGGACCCCAGCAGUUUUCAUUCCAGUAGUCAGUUUAGUGAAGAUUUUUGCUUUGCUUGCUUUGUGGAAUGCUUUUGUGAUUGGAUCUCUGCCCACUGUGCUUGAUCAGGCAGAACAAGUCGGGCACUGAUCACAACAGUCACCUAACAAGCUCCCUAUUUAAUGCAGGUGUAGCCCCCCCACAUCCCCUUUUUCUCCCUGCUAUAGAAAACUUGCCAUACACAAACUCACAUUUGCAGCGUGGACACAUUAAAGAGUGAUCAUUAAAACAACAAAAGGAUGCUUUGGCUUGCCAAAGGAUUCAAUUCAGACCUCUUUUAAACUGUGAGUUCCCUCCCCAACACACACACAUACACACACACACAAACACACAUGAUCACCACUGCUACCAUAAUCAUACGUUUAAAAUAUAUAAUUUCAUUUCCAAGUCUUUAAUCCAUAAUAAGAUUUUCAAGAGUAGAUCUACUUUAUUCUGUAGAAUAUACCUGAAAAUUGAUCUCAAUCUAUUGUUUGAGUCUAACUAUUGAAGACACCAUUUAUAAUUUUGAUGUAGAUGAUACACAGUUGCCUGUGUCCCUGUAGUACUUUCAAAAGGACCAGUUUUCAUAGAGGUUUAUUUUAAGAAGUUUAAGAUUUAAAUAGUGAAAUCUUACUGUUCCUUGAAUAAAUUCUGACUUCCCAAGGAAUACCUAGACACAAUGAUCAUUAUUUUAGCAUAAAUUCCUGAUUUAUGACUUUGUAGCUAUUUUGGAGAUUUAACAUUCUGUAAAUGCAUUGUUUAUUGAGGAAAUUCCUAGCUUUAUUGAGUGACUUUAGCAAGGAAGCUCUAUCUCACAGGGAGGCAGGCGCUUAGGUUGAAAUAAGAGAAUCAACGUGGAAGCACUUUGGAAUGUUAAAGCACUUUACAAAUGUAAGAUAUUUUUAGUGUCAUUGGAUUAAUACUGAAGUGAAAUUUCGGCAGUUUAAACUGAUUCAGUUUCUUGCAAAAUAAUUGAUCUUGAGGGUGAUUCCUGCACAUAAUUUGCUGAAAUACAUGAAAGGAAUGGUGGGGAUUGCCGGCGGGGGGGUGCGGGGGUGGGGGUGGUGGUGGUGGUGGUGGUGGUGUUGAUGGUGGUGAAACAACCCAUUGUAGGAAAUGACUUUGGUUAGCAUUUUAAUGUAAAUUGUAUGGUAGAAUGUUGUCUGUGAAGUGUUAAGAACAAGCUGAAUGAUUCUGAUCCUUUUUUAUUGUAAAGCUGUAGAAUAAUUUUCACUCAUUUCUGAUCUCUAUUUUCCUAUCUAACAUUAAAACAAAAACAAUCACGUUAGGAAACAAAAACAUAAUGCUUUGACAGAGGAACAAAUACCAUCUUUAUUAGAAGUUAUGUAUUUCAAAAAGUCAUUUUAAUUGAUGGCAGGUGCUUAGAACAGUGCCUGGCAUAUAGUAAGUACUAUACAUGAAUUAUUUUACAGUUAUUGCCAUUGUUAUUGUUGCUACUGUUAUUAUUACAUUUAGAAAAACAAACCUAAAUUAAGAUUCUCCAUCUGAAAAUCUCACUUUUCAGUUAGUCUUUACUUGCAUUUAAAAUACUUUACAUUAUUGUUCAGUUGGCAUGUUUAUAGAUUACCAUUUAAGUGAAGUGAGAUUAUAAAUCUGUGAGACAGCUGUUCUCAUGUAACACAAAAUUAAUAUGUAAUUCCAUUUACCUACAGUCACAUUGCGUAUAAGUAAGUACAGUAAAGGAAUUUACUCAAGUCGAUUAGAAAGAAACACCCAGAAGUAUAACCUUAGACAUGACUGUAUUAAUAAAUGAAAUAAUUUUUAAUCAUUUAUUAAAGAUGAAGUCUUCACAUUUUAAACACAUAGGUUAUAGGCAUUAGCAUUUAGGAGAAGAAUGUUGUUUCUUAUGCAGUUUAGUUUGACUGUUAACCUAUGUAUGACUAUUUGCUUCUUUUUCUACCUUACCUGAUGUACAAUUCAUAGUUCAAAAUGACUUGAGGUGAACAUUUUCCUGGUUUUUUUAUUCAAGAGAUGGGAGGAUAUAAAAGGGCAGCUCUAGGAGGGGUGAGAGAAUCGGUCAGCCAAAUUAGUAAUGUUAUGAUGGCACUUGGUAUUAAAAAGCAAAAAAAAAAAACUUUAGUAAUUAAUUUUUCAGUGUUAGACACUGUUAUCACCAUGAAGGAAUCAUGCUUCUUUUGAGUGUACUACUGCCAAACUUGUUGCUAUCAGUUAUAGGCACUAAGAGCACAUUGUUUUUAUUCCAUUGAAGUUAAUUAUUAUAAAAAUUUCCAUAUAGCAGAAAUUUCCCAGCUACCAUUGACGGAUCAUUUAUUUUAGGUAAUAUUCAACACCUCAAAAUUGGACAGUGUUUGGACUAAUGAGGUAUUUGUCCUCUAACAAUUAAAGAGGACUUCACUUAAUUAAAGUUAACUAAAGUUGUUCACAAUCAUUAUUCAUUUGCAUUCAUUCUAUUUUAAGAGUGAUGUUUUCAGGGUAAAAAUUUCAACUACUAGCAAAAUACUUACCUUAAACAAGGACCAGAACUUUAAUUAAGCACACCAGAAUGUCACACAUGUAUAAAAAUUCGAACGAGAUCUCUUACUUUCUUUUUCUCUCCCUAAUCCCCUGUUUUGGGAACAAACUUAGGCUUCUCAGAGUGACAAAAAAAUAAUUCCUGUGGGAAUAGAUGUGGCUGACGAGUGUAGGGAGAACUAAGGAAUAGUUUAUGUGAUUUAAAAGGGUCUAUUGUUAAAUUGUCAAAUUGUUGAUUGAGGAAAUGCUUUCCAGUUGCAGAUUGCCUUAUAGUUUGCAAAGCACAUUCACAUUCAUUAUUUUACUGAUGGAUGGUAAGUACUGGAAAUGAAGCCCAUGUUGAGAAUUUUCCCAAGAUCAAAAAGGUAAGUGGCAGAGCUGAAAAUCUAACUCAUACAUCUGAUUUCAAGUCCAGCACUCCACCCAACACAUGACACCUCCCUUUAAUCAGGUGUUUAGUCUGUUAUUUUCCCACUGGUGACAGAUUAUUACAUGGUUAAUGAUUAGGAAAAAAUUACAAGUUUGCUUUCACUUGAUAGUAGCAAAUUUUGUUGUAAGUAAUUCAUUCAGAGCAUUAUAACUGUGGACUAUCUUCCAGGACCUGGGUAAUUUUAUUACAUUGAACUGUUUGCCCUGGCUCUUAGAAUAAAAGAAUUUGACUUGUGCUGGAAUUGAAUGUUUUAAAUCUGAUAUAGGGAGGAGUUGGUUAAUCUUCACUGCCCAAACACAAAUAGUGUAUGUAUCUAUUUAGAUCCCACAGAAACAUUGAAAGGAAAGAAAGUGAAUUGAGGGUGCAUUCAGUAAAUUUCCAUUAAUGGUCAUUUCUUUAACUGAAGUUAGAUUUCUUUGAUUUUCCUAAUAAUUCAUUGACAUUUGGGAGUUAUAGCAAAAAGUCUUUUCAUUUAAUUUCUUCCUUCAUUAUAAAAUUUGGUAUUCUGAUCUAAAUCAGCACAGUAGGCAAAACAGGAUAAAGUAAGACAGGUGGAAGAAUAAGCAGUGUAGCAAUAGACGUUCUUCAUUUGUUUAAAAAGUGAACUUGCUUUUGGCAGUCAGGCAAGUAGAUUUUAGAAGCCUUGAAAAUCAAACUCUCUCCUUGGGACAUAGAAAUCCCUGUUUACAAUUAAGUUCAUUUUGAUUUAGCACCUUUUUUAAGGCUUUAAGAGUAUAUAAAAAUAGCCCAGACGUUUUAUUGGCAGUAUUGGAAAAUAGCUUUUGUAAAAUGCUUAAUUAAAACUUUCAGUAUAUUUUCUCUAAGAGGUGCUGCCAGACUCUUAGAUAGUGAGGAUCAUUUACUAGAAAACGUUGCUUGGUCUUGAAUGAGAAAUGAGAAAUUUAAGACACUGCUUUUUAUAAUAAUGAAAUAAAUACAUCACAAAGCACUGAGUUUUUGCCACAAUCAUUGGAUUGCUGAUUUUAAAGCUAUUGAUAAAAUUGCCAAGAAAAAUGUGCUUGCCAUAUGAACUUAAAAUAUAUUCUCCAGCAAUUCUGCAUUGAUUAUUGGUAAUGUAGCUACAGGUCUCACAUUUCCACCUUAUUUUGGAAAAAUAGACUCAACACUUGAGAAAUAGGAAUGUUUAAAGAUGUUUCUAGUGUAAAUUAUAUACUGUUUUAGAUAUGCAUUUUUAGAGGGUACCUUUCAACUUCUGGCUGAAUAAUUAAUUUCUUUUAGAAUGGAAAACAUGUACUUAAAUACUUAUUAAGUGAAAUGAGAAAGUUACUGCUAUUUUCUCUUAGCUUCCUGAUACCUCUUUCUUAUUGGUUAGGGUUGCAUUGGUUGUGUUCUGUGAGUCUUACCCUCAUGUGCCCUUUGCCAAACUUGUGCCCUUGAAUUCAGGCAAACAUGCCCUUUCCUGGUCUCUCUCUGGCUGAAAAGGUGAGGGCCACUGUGGGAGUCCUGCAGGGCCCAUAGAGGGCUUCGCCAGAUGUUGAUCACUCCCAGUACACAGCCUUCUUGCACUUAGCUUGCAGAGGCAACCUUCCUUGUAGGGAUCCUUGUUGUACAGAUCCAAGGCUGUGCUGCCUGCCCUACUGUCACUUGGCACAGAAGCAGCUGGGCCGGUGUUUAAAGCUAUUUUCAUGGUUGGAUUGAUCACAAUAUGUUUGAUGCCAGCCACACCUUCUGGAUUUACCGAAUAUCUAAUUCCCUAUAUAUUGUAGUCACUUUAGCUAGUUUUGACAAUUUAUAUAAUUUUUCUCCUAUGAUUAAUAAUUUCCUACUUAUAGACUUGAAACUUAGAAUAACAGUGAAGUUUCCAUCUCACAAUUAAUCUUGAAAAUUGCUCACAUGUGUAUCCAUGGGGCCCUUGAAAGUCUGACCAGCAAAUGUGAUUUUUUACUCUUGCUUUUUAAAGUUUUAUGCCUCCAGUCUUGAAAGCUUACCAACCUUGUCCUCGCACUCAGAGUCCUGUGCCCCCACCCACCUCCAUGAUGAAGUCCUUAUUGUUGCUGCAGCUUUUACCAUAGUUUCCCUUCGGCUGUCACCCUGCCUCCGACUCUUCCAACUGGUUGAGUAUGGGGGACACAAUUCCUAUUGCCAUGGCUGGAAGACAUAUAUUCCUGGAGUCUCAAACUGAAACUUCACAUACAUCUUCCCUCAGAAAUGAUGACUGGGUAUAGUCAAAAUAGUUCUCUGUUAGUUCAGGAGUUGCAUAGGUUAAAUAUAGGCAUAUCUAGACAAAGCUAUAAACCUAUCCACCAUUAAUUUAUGACAUUGUUUCUACAAGAUAAUUUAUUCUGAGUUUCAACUAAACAAUGACCUUGGAAUAUGUCUGUUUUGUAAAUUUGAAACUGCCUAUAUUAGAAUUCUAGUAACUUGCAUUCUUUAAGUUGGCAGUAACUAGGCAGCAGAGUGAAGUGGCCCAUGUGUGUGUUGGGAAGUAGUGGAGAAGCUGACCUACCAUGAAAAUCCUGUAGCUGAUCUCCAUAGAGUUUGUAUCCAGAUACUCAAGACUGGAAUGCACAUGCAUAAGUGGCCCAGGGCCUGCUAACAAAGGGCAGGUGUAAAACGAUUGAGCUGACCUUUGAGGAGAUGGGGGUUUACAAGUGUCAUACAUUUCCCUUACAGAUUCUUUUGAGCAUUCUGUCCCAAAACUAUUGCCAUUGUGGGAACAAAGGUAUUUUAUCAUCCGAUCUAUGAAGGAGAUAAUAGUCUGGUAUAAUUGGUGUUGUAAAGACUAGCAGCGAUUAUUACUAGUUUUUAGCCUUGAGCAAUAGCACUUAAUUUUAUCAAGUCCUAGAGAGUCAUCCUCCUCUACAAUCACAGGGCACAGAAAAGUAUGAUGAUCCUUUCUUAUUGAGAAAAAACAAAAAAACCUACAUAUACUCCAGAGACAAUGCUAAGCUAACUAAUAUAAUUGCAUUAUUAUACAUUCAUCUUUGGCAUGUAUGCUUCAACAUAUCUUUCUUUGCUUCCCUUUUUUUUUUUUUUUUUGGUGCUUUACUUGGUUGCCCCUGCUUAUGUGAGCUCCAGUUGAUCACAGGGGUGCAGGGAUAGCAUGUUGUCAAAUGAACAGAGUGAGGAAUUUGCAAAAACCCUUGAAAAACAUUUUUGAGCUCCAGGAAAAUUGGAGCUGAAAAGAUAACUAAGACAAUAAGUUUGCAGAAAGGGAAAAGAGAAUGAGAGAAUAACAAUAUAUUGUUAUAGGUUCACCUUUCUCUGAGCAGAGGAAAUACUGCUGUUUCGGACUUCAAAAUGUAAUAGAGGCAUAUUUAUGAUUCAUAUAAAGAGGUCUGAAAUACCCUGGAGGAACUGCCUACUUGGCUCACCCUACAAAUUUCCAGGGAUAUUGAAGUCAUCUGUGCAUUAUUAGCGUAUUAAAGAUUAAUGUUCAGGUUUAUAUCAUUAUAUAACUCGAAACAGAAAAGUUUACUUCAUUUGUUUUUGAGAAAAAAAAGUUCCCUGCCAGAUUUUGGUAGGAGGAGUAGGGAAAUAUUUUGACUCAUCAGAGUCCACUGAGGUUUUCUAUAUUACAGAGAAAAAUUACCUGAAGAGUAUACCACCCAUUAAAAAGGGUGAAAUUAACUUGUUGUUUAAAAGACCUUUGAUUAAUUGGGAAAAUAAGAAUAUACAAUAAGGUAAGUAUUUAUAACCUGUCAGUAUCAAAUGGGAAUAAUACAUCCAAAACAGACCACAUUAUUACAAGCAUCACCAUUUACCUUGCUGAUGGUGAAAUCACAUAAAAAUGAACGGGAGACAAAUCUAAGGUAUGACUUUUAGCCCUUUAAUAUUCAUUUUGCAGACUGUUCACAACCAAGUUUUAAUCUCGAAUUGCUUUCCUUUGCCACCCAGCAAGCUUCUGAGUUGCUUCCUUACGCUGUUCUUUGGAAUGUGCCCCGGGAAUGUAAACUCAUUUUAAUAUUGGCCUAAGUAAAAUAGGAUUAUAAAGGCAAAUCUGUGGCUCAAGUUCCCAUAAUGCAUUUCAAAAGCAAGUUAAAUUAUUUUGGGAUUAUCCUGUUUGGGAUAACAUUAUUCCUUUCUACUAGCAUAGUUAAUCAAGAAUUGACAAAUGUAUUUUGUGAAGUAAACAUGAAAUUACACAAUUAUUUGUCACUUUUUAUUAAGUUACCAAACAUUCACUUAAUGCUGGUGUAGGUGUUAUAGGAAAGCAAUGGCAAUAUGAAUCAAAUUUUAGUAGAGGCUCUGUCAUUUAAAAAAAGGAAAGAGAAAGAAAAACAACUCCAAUAAAAGCAAAUGUUCCUAAUCUUAGUAUAAUGCCAAUAGGGUAGUUAUAUGGAGCUUAAUUUGCAGGUUUCUGGGAAAAUAUAUAUGAAAUCCAGUGUAUCAUAUAAGACAGCAAGAAGUCCCUUUUAAAGCACAUGCAAUGUGCUAUAUAUGGACAUAUGAAAAUAUUUUUGGUAUUAAAACAAAAUAGUAAACUAAACUAGGUGAAAUACCUUCCUAACCUUAAAUAUCUAUUUUAAAAUGUAGCUGAUAUCUGAUAACACUGUAAUACUGGUACUGGUCUAGCCUAAUUUUGCAGCGAAUUAACAGUUACUAAUAUGCAGUCUCACAGUUAACUGUGGUUAUCACAGACUCCUUUCUUCCUGUGUAGAACUAGAUACAUAAAAUGUAAAAUUUCCUAAACCCACUGCUGACAGGAAAGCUUAAUACCUUUACUAAUCUAUGGCAUUUUUUUGAGACAGGGUCUCACUCUGUCACCCAGGCUAGAGUGUAGUUGCGCGACAGGGUUUCACCAUGUUGCCCAGGCUGUUCUUGAAAUCCUGGCCUCAAGGGAUCCACCUGCCUUGGCCUCCCAAAGUGCUGGGAUUAUAGGCAUGAGCCACCAUGGCUAGCAUUUUUUUAAACUUCUAAUCUACAAGAACAAACCUAUACAUUGAAUCUUAAUGAAGAGACACAACUAGUAAGAGGGAAAUGUACUGUUCCCACUCAGUGCUUCAUCCAGCUGCAAAUUUGUUACAUUUUAAAAAUCCUUGAGCCCAGGAGUCUGGGUGGGGCUGCAGUGAGCCAUAAUGAUGCCACUGCUCUUCACCCUGGGCAGCAUAGUGAGACCUCAUCUCUUUAAAAAAAUUGUAAAACCUUUGAUGAGAAAAUGAAUACUUAAAAUGUAUAUUUCCAGUUUAAUAGACAAUCUUGUACUUGAAGCCCACUCUGGGGGAUGUUUUCCAUGGAUUCUUUUAAGAUGUCUCAAAUAAAAUAGAAUACUUGGUACUUUGUGGUGACCUGAUCUUAAGGUAACACUGGCAUCCCAUAAUCAAUUUGCUGAUCAUUUAUUCCUAUCCCUUCUCUGGUCCAGCACCUUCUUCUAUGUAUCUGAUCACCCCCUGCCACACUCCCCAUUAUGCACCCACUCAAAAGCAGAAAGCCAAGAGAAUAAUGCUGGAACUUUUUUCUUUUAUUAAACAGAUGGGAAUUUCAAGUCUCCUUUGCAGGUAUGACUUUGUUCUAUUAGAAGAAAUUCAAUGAUUGAGUCUAGAGACCAUCACCAAUGCUGUACUUAAAUCCUAUGACUUGUGCCACAUAACCUGGUGAAGGCAGAGUCAAACAUGUAGAAGAAGAAGAAAAAAAUCUGUUUCUCUGCACAAUGCCUGGCUCACUCUUGGGCUCCACUGGAAGAAAGUAGAACAGUGCACGCACGUGCAAAGAUGCUGUCCACCAGAAAUGUCAGUGACAGCCUGGGGGCAAGAAGAAUAACUGCCCUUGUGUCUUUGCCCAGCUGAUAUUCCUCACAGGCAGCCAGCAGAGUUGAUUAACCAUGUCCAUGCCCAGGCAGUCUCCUCUGUAUAUCUCUCAAAAACUUCUAGUUAGAUUUUGUUUUGUUUUGUGUUGUUUUGUUUUAAAACAGGGUGGGGGUGACAGCUCUCCACAUUAAUUCUGCAAGUAACUUUUGUUUUAUUAUCUUUUUCCUAGAGUGAUUAUAUUGCCACAAAAACACAUUUUAGAAGAAAAGUGAUGCUUAUGGAAUUUUAUCUUCGUCUACUCCAGAUCUGCCUAAAGGAAAGAAAACUCAGAGGCUUCUGAGUAGAAAGCAACCCAAAUUUCUACAAGCCUACAAGUGGACUCUGGCAAUUGAAUGAUCCUAUUCAUGCAGAUCAUUCAUACUGCUGCUUAUGGAUCCAGUGAUUUCUAAUUAACAAUAUUUACACUGUGCUUUGUUUUUUGUUUUCUGGUUUUCCUCCCCAGUCUGUCCCUUUGAAAGGAAACAGAUACUAUACAAGUGAGCAUCUCAUAACUCUUUCCCUCUUUAAAAAAAAGUAACUUAGAAUACAUAUAAAUUUGGUCAAUGCCAAUUUUAAUAAUGUAAAAUAUUUAGAUUCAAUUUUGAAGUUGAAAAACUUUAAACCAGGGCACAUAAAGAAAAAACAGCUGUCAUAAUUGGAAGGAAGGUAUGAUCUGGAAUCUUUUUUCCGAGUAUUACACACACAAAACAUUUCUUGAUCAAUGAAUUAAAUGUCAACUGAACUGAUAUCUUGAUGGGGCAUUACCAGUAUUUUAAAGGCAGGACUAAAGGGCAGAUUAUUUCAAGUUUUGCUCAUUAGCAAAACUGCAACAUUCUGCUCAUGUUAUAUGUCAAUGAAACUAAUAUCUUGAUUGAGCAUUUCCAACAUUUUAAAGGCAGAACUGAGAAACAGCUAUUUGUUCACAUACAACACUGUGAUGUUCUGCCUGAAAAUCGAUUGAGUAUUUCCAAACCUAUUAUUUUUCAUUUAUUGUGAAACCUACAUUUACCUCCUAAAAGAAACAAAGCUCUUCAAAAGUCUCUUCCCAAGGCCCCUCCCUGCUUCUCUGGGCCUCUCCCCACUUUCAACCUCUAUUCUACUUUUUCUUAUUCUUUCUCCAUUUUCCCCAAUGCACACUCUUCCUCUUAUGCCCAUGGCUACUAUAAAGAGAUCAAUUUCCCAUAUUCAAGAAAUUAGUGUUUACUUAUCAAUCAAUAUUCUGACAAAAACUUAAGCCAAAAAGAACCUCUUAUAAGGCCUUGUUUCCUUCUGGAUAUUGAGCCAAUAUAAGAUGUACCAAAUUAAAAAAAAAAAUCAGAGCAAGCUCCCCCCCGUUCUAUUUUUGCUUGCCUCUGAUGUAAACUGAAUUAAGAUUUUAGGUACCUGGACCUUUGAGAACGUGACACUAGCAAGGUGGUGACCACAGAGAAUAGGUACAAAGGUCUUGAAGCUUGCUUAGAGCUUUGUUCCGUGGUGGCACACAAAUCUUGGCUUGCUGUACCAUCAUUGGCAAACCUCAUCAUAUCACAGUUGGGUGUGUUUGUAUGUGUGUGAGCACUAGUGUGUGUGUGUACAUAUUCGUGUGUAUGCACACUUUGUGUACCUGUGUACAUGUGAUUGUAGAUGUACCUGUUGUGUGUAAACUCUGUUAAAAUGAAAUUUGCUUCGCAUUUAAUGUGCAACUUUGAAGUAGUGUAAUAUUUAUCUAAAGGUUUUCACUACUUGGUUUUAAUGUCUUUGAACGUGUACUUCUAUCUUCAAGCAAGCUUAUAGUACGUGUUGCUAAACUAACUUUUCCAAAGAACCGAGUUGACUUCUAUUUUUCCUUGCCUACCAACCAAAGGGAUGGUGGGCUCUUUUUUCCCUCUUGUAAAUUGUGCUGAGGAGAGGACGUGGCUAUGAGAUCAGUCAUUGUUCCAGUUACUGGUCACUGCUAGGGCAUCAACUUUAUCAGUUCCUUCAGACUCUUCUCUUUUUCCAACCUAAUCAAAUAACGCAGUGUGGCUUUUGUUCAUUAUAACAACGCGCUCUUUAGGCAACUUUUUUUCAAGCCUUCUGUCACCAUUUUAUUUUUUCAAGUAAGUUAAGUAAUAAUUGUUCAGAAUUGUGGGAAAAAAGAUUACUUGGGGGAAAAUACUGUAUCACUUUAUUUGCAUAUUAGGUUCAGAAGCUGCCAGCAGACAGGGUACAGAGGGUACAGCACAGAUGUAACAGUUGCUGAAUAAAUGAAUGAGAAACCUCAUACACAGUAGUACGUAUUAUACAAAUAGUAACAGGUACACAUAGUCACAGGUACUGCAUAACAAAUGCAAUCUUGUUCUCAUUAUUUAUUAGUUUACAGACAAUUAAUUUAUUCAGUAUUGUGCUGGAAGAAUCUUUGUGGAAUAUGUUUACCAACUUAUCACUUACCUUCCAGCUAUCAGUUCAUGCUGCUAAGAAAAAACAAUGAUGGAAUAUUUUUGUGUGUGUGACCUCUACAUUUAAUUUGAUAUCAGGCAUAGUCACUUGGUCGUUAAAAACUGAAACUUUACAGUUCCACCAGCUAAUUACAUCUGCUAUUUCUGCUUCACAGAUAUGCUUUGAGUUGCUUUGGCUUUGUCUUCCUUUGUAAAUACUCUUGUACUUUCUUUUCCUUGUAAACAUCUCGUUUGCAGUUUUGGGAGACGACUUUGCAACUCUGUAUAGUGUUUAUAUAUAUAUGUAUAUCUAUAUAUAUCUGACUUGCCUUUCCAUACAGCUACUCACAAUAAAUGUGUUCAUGUAAAUUA